GAGUCAUAGGCGCACCUGCCAGGUUCACCUGCAGCCACUUGGCUCAGUGGGACUGGCGGGCGUGAUGCGCCCGUGGGUGGAGAUGGGUGUUCAUCCCCCAUCCCUCGGAGCAUCUGGACCUGGCGUUUCAUUGCAUGUAAAAUGGGACAGGAACACGCACCUCGGUUCAUGUGCUUGAGGAGUGUUUAGUGAGCACCUGCUAUGCGCCAGGCCUUUGGGCAGUGGACACAGGGAUAUGGCCGGGAUGAUAGACAGGUUCAGCCCUGCCAACACAGGCAUCCGGUCUUGGGAUGUCGAUCCUGGCGUCUGCAACCUUGAUGAACAGCUCAAGGUCUUUGUGUCCCGACACUCUGCCACCUUCUCCAGCAUUGUGAAAGGCCAGCGGAGCCUGCACCACCGUGGAGACAACCUGGAGACCCUGGUCCUCCUGAACCCAUCAGACAAGUCCCUGUAUGAUGAGCUCCGGAACCUUCUGUUGGACCCUGCCUCUCACAAGCUACUGGUGUUGGCUGGGCCCUGCCUGGAGGAGACGGGGGAGCUGCUGCUACAGACAGGGGGCUUCUCGCCUCACCACUUCCUCCAGGUCCUGAAGGACAGAGAGAUCCGGGACAUCCUGGCCACCACGCCCCCACCUGUGCAGCCGCCCAUACUCACCAUCACCUGCCCCACCUUCGGUGACUGGGCUCAGCUGGCACCCGCUGUGCCUGGCCUUCAGGGGGCGCUCCGGCUCCAGCUGCGGCUGAACCCCCCGGCGCAGCUGCCCAACUCUGAGGGCCUGUGCGAAUUCCUGGAGUACGUGGCUGAGUCUCUGGAGCCACCGUCCCCCUUCGAGCUGCUGGAGCCCCCGACCUCCGGGGGCUUCCUCAGGCUGGGCCGGCCCUGCUGCUACAUCUUCCCUGGAGGCCUCGGGGAUGCCGCCUUCUUCGCCGUCAAUGGCUUCACUGUGCUGGUCAACGGUGGCUCAAACCCCAAGUCCAGUUUCUGGAAGCUGGUGCGGCACCUGGACCGCGUGGAUGCCGUGCUGGUGACCCACCCUGGCGCCGACAGCCUCCCCGGCCUCAACAGCCUGCUGCGGCGCAAACUGGCGGAGCGCUCCGAGGUGGCUGCUGGUGGGGGCUCCUGGGACGACAGGCUGCGCAGGCUCAUCUCCCCCAACCUGGGGGUCGUGUUCUUCAACGCCUGCGAGGCCGCGUCGCGGCUGGCGCGCGGCGAGGAUGAGGCGGAGCUGGCGCUGAGCCUCCUGGCGCAGCUGGGCAUCACGCCUCUGCCACUCAGCCGCGGCCCCGUGCCAGCCAAACCCACCGUGCUCUUCGAGAAGAUGGGCGUGGGCCGGCUGGACAUGUAUGUGCUGCACCCGCCCUCCGCCGGCGCCGAGCGCACGCUGGCCUCUGUGUGCGCCCUGCUGGUGUGGCACCCCGCCGGCCCCGGCGAGAAGGUGGUGCGCGUGCUGUUCCCCGGUUGCACCCCGCCCGCCUGCCUCCUGGACGGCCUGGUCCGCCUGCAGCACUUGAGGUUCCUGCGAGAGCCCGUGGUGACGCCCCAGGACCUGGAGGGGCCGGGGCGAGCCGAGAGCAAAGAGAGCGUGGGCUCCCGGGACAGCUCGAAGAGAGAGGGCCUCCUGGCCACCCACCCUAGACCUGGCCAGGAGCGCCCUGGGGUGGCCCGCAAGGAGCCAGCACGGGCUGAGGCCCCACGCAAGACUGAGAAAGAAGCCAAGACCCCCCGGGAGUUGAAGAAAGACCCCAAACCGAGUGUCUCCCGGACCCAGCCGCGGGAGGUGCGCCGGGCAGCCUCUUCUGUGCCCAACCUCAAGAAGACGAAUGCCCAGGCGGCACCCAAGCCCCGCAAAGCGCCCAGCACGUCCCACUCUGGCUUCCCGCCGGUGGCAAAUGGACCCCGCAGCCCGCCCAGCCUCCGAUGUGGAGAAGCCAGCCCCCCCAGUGCAGCCUGCGGCUCUCCGGCCUCCCAGCUGGUGGCCACGCCCAGCCUGGAGCUGGGGCCGAUCCCAGCCGGGGAGGAGAAGGCACUGGAGCUGCCUUUGGCCGCCAGCUCAAUCCCAAGGCCACGCACACCCUCCCCUGAGUCCCACCGGAGCCCCGCAGAGGGCAGCGAGCGGCUGUCGCUGAGCCCACUGCGGGGCGGGGAGGCCGGGCCAGACGCCUCACCCACAGUGACCACACCCACGGUGACCACGCCCUCACUACCCGCAGAGGUGGGCUCCCCGCACUCGACCGAGGUGGACGAGUCCCUGUCGGUGUCCUUUGAGCAGGUGCUGCCGCCAUCCGCCCCCACCAGUGAGGCUGGGCUGAGCCUCCCGCUGCGUGGCCCCCGGGCGCGGCGCUCGGCUUCCCCACACGAUGUGGACCUGUGCCUGGUGUCACCCUGUGAAUUUGAGCAUCGCAAGGCGGUGCCAAUGGCACCGGCACCUGCGUCCCCCGGCAGCUCGAAUGACAGCAGUGCCCGGUCACAGGAACGGGCAGGUGGGCUGGGGGCCGAGGAGACGCCACCCACAUCGGUCAGCGAGUCCCUGCCCACCCUGUCUGACUCGGAUCCCGUGCCCCUGGCCCCCGGUGCGGCAGACUCAGACGAAGACACAGAGGGCUUUGGAGUCCCUCGCCACGACCCUUUGCCUGACCCCCUCAAGGUCCCCCCACCACUGCCUGACCCAUCCAGCAUCUGCAUGGUGGACCCCGAGAUGCUGCCCCCCAAGACAGCACGGCAAACGGAGAACGUCAGCCGCACCCGGAAGCCCCUGGCCCGCCCCAACUCACGCGCUGCCGCCCCCAAAGCCACUCCAGUGGCUGCUGCCAAAACCAAGGGGCUUGCUGGUGGGGACCGUGCCAGCCGACCACUCAGUGCCCGGAGUGAGCCCAGUGAGAAGGGAGGCCGGGCACCCCUGUCCAGAAAGUCCUCAACCCCCAAGACUGCCACUCGAGGCCCGUCGGGGUCAGCCAGCAGCCGGCCCGGGGUGUCAGCCACCCCACCCAAGUCCCCGGUCUACCUGGACCUGGCCUACCUGCCCAGCGGGAGCAGCGCCCACCUGGUGGAUGAGGAGUUCUUCCAGCGCGUGCGCGCGCUCUGCUACGUCAUCAGUGGCCAGGACCAGCGCAAGGAGGAAGGCAUGCGGGCCGUCCUGGACGCGCUACUGGCCAGCAAGCAGCAUUGGGACCGUGACCUGCAGGUGACCCUGAUCCCCACUUUCGACUCGGUGGCCAUGCAUACGUGGUACGCAGAGACGCACGCCCGGCACCAGGCGCUGGGCAUCACGGUGUUGGGCAGCAACAGCAUGGUGUCCAUGCAGGAUGACGCCUUCCCGGCCUGCAAGGUGGAGUUCUAGCCCCAUCGCCGACACGCCCCCCACUCAGCCCAGCCCGCCUGUCCCUAGAUUCAGCCACAUCAGAAAUAAACUGUGACUACACUUG